GAGUUUUCCGCGGCCGGCCGCUGCUCAGCCGCUGUCGCUCCGGCUCCGGCUGCGGCUGCCGCUGCCGAGGCUGCUGCGCGGCGCCUGGCGGGCUCGGGACGCGCGGGCCGGGGCCGAGGGCUCUGGGCGCCGAGAUGGAGCCGCUGGCGCCCAUGCGGCUCUACACGCUCUCCAAGCGCCACUUUGUCCUCGUGUUUGUCGUCUUCUUCAUCUGCUUUGGCCUGACCAUCUUCGUUGGGAUCAGAGGACCUAAAGUGAUCCAGACUUCUGCGGCUAAUUUUUCACUAAAUAAUAGCAAAAAGCUAAAGCCAAUUCAAAUACUUUCAAAUCCACUGUCUACAUACAAUCAGCAACUAUGGCUGACAUGUGUUGUUGAGUUGGAUCAAUCAAAAGAAACUUCUAUUAAGACAAGCUUUCCCAUGACUGUUAAAGUCGAUGGUGUAGCUCAAGAUGGAACCACGAUGUACAUUCAUAACAAAGUUCACAACCGGACAAGGACCCUCACAUGUGCAGGGAAAUGUGCGGAGAUUAUUGUGGCUCACCUUGGCUACCUGAACUACACUCAGUAUACAGUGAUAGUGGGAUUUGAACACCUGAAGCUCCCCAUCAAGGGAAUGAACUUCACAUGGAAGACUUAUAACCCUGCCUUCUCCCGGUUGGAAAUCUGGUUCCGGUUUUUCUUUGUGGUGCUCACCUUCAUCGUCACUUGCCUGUUUGCGCAUUCCCUCCGGAAAUUUUCCAUGAGAGACUGGGGCAUCGAGCAGAAGUGGAUGUCUGUUCUCCUGCCUCUGCUGCUACUUUACAAUGAUCCGUUCUUCCCCCUCUCCUUCCUGGUCAACAGCUGGCUCCCAGGGAUGCUGGAUGACCUCUUUCAGUCCAUGUUCCUGUGCGCCCUGCUGCUCUUCUGGCUGUGCGUGUACCACGGGAUUCGUGUCCAGGGAGAAAGAAAGUGUUUAACUUUCUAUUUGCCUAAAUUCUUCAUUGUUGGACUAUUGUGGUUGGCUUCUGUUACGCUAGGAAUAUGGCAAACACGAAUAGGAGGGUGACUUUAGUCACAGGCUGCUCAAAAACACAGGCUGCAGAGAACAGGAUUUGGAUUGGCAAACUCAUUGUACCCUCAUGUCACACUCCUUCUUUGCUCCUACCUUGGAGCAUUUUGGCUGGGAGGCAAAACCCCAAUGCUAUUACAGGCAGUCCCCUUACCCCUCAUUCCACACCCACUACCCAGAAACUGAAGCCUCAUGACCCGCUUUGAGGAAAAAUAUCCCGUCCUGGUUUUCUGUGUUCCAGUCGGCCUUCCAAACACAUCCUCCCCCUGGGACACAGACUUCAGGCCAGCCUGUAUUACGUCAGGUUGCUAGUUGCCCUUUUCUGGGAGACUCCCAAUGACUGUGCCCUCUCUGCUUAAAGACUGUAGAGGCAACUGGUGUUCUCACGCAAAGUGGCCAGGGUGUGGGAGACUAGAUCUUUGACUCUGGCAGUCUCCAGGACUGUAUGCAAGGCCAGGCCCAGGUGGGCAUACUGGCAAAGGCUUUUGGGAACCCGGCUAGGGAGGAAGUAGGGAGCAUCCGUUUCCAUGAUGAUUCUCUCCAGUGGGAUCUGCCUCAGCACUUCCCGGGCUUCUCAGGUGGAGGAGUACGUCAGGACUGCCAUGAGGCCCACCGACGUUGGGAAAGUACUUCAGCAGGGGUUCCAUGGCCAGGUAGCUGCAGUGAAGCAAUGCUUGUGUAUCUUGUAGUCAGAGAACACACAUUUUCUCAUGGUGUCCAGCAGAUCCUCGUCAGCUUGCUGGCAGAGGAUCACCAAAGCUUCUCUAGAGACGCAGCCAGCUCAAGCUGUCUCUUAAAUACCUUGUGAUGUUCUGGGACAGGCAUGGUGCACUUGUAGGAGUAAUUGAAGCCUGUUUCUCCAAAUGCCACAGUCGUGGGGUGCCUUAAGGCUUGUAAAAGAUUUCUUUCCUGACUCUUAUUGUAGUAACAUGGAAAAUGAGGGUGACAGCCAAAGGCCCCCCAGACCAGAUUCUCUUUCAACAGCUCCCCCCGUAGGCAAUUUGUCAGGGUGAGGGUGGCAGAGGUCAGAGAUGCAACCCUGAAAUUCCUUAGAGAAGGAGCUGCUGUAAAUUCUUCUGAACUUAGUCAAGGUCCCUUUGAAAGACAACUUGGAAUACAGCAUAUCCAAAUGACAGUGGGUAUCAGUGAAGCCCUGCUCUAGGCUUGGCUCCCAGUGGCUCUUUGGCAGGGAGCUGGAUGUGUGUCCUCCACAAGGACACAGAGGCAUCUCCUCUUGGAAUGUUCUUCUUUGCUUCACCUCUUUUCCUCCCGAGCUUCUGGAGAAGUGAAAUGAGUGAGAAUUCUGGGAGCUGCCUUCCUCUGAGGCCUCCACAUCUCUGGAGACGUUAUGGGCGCUCACUGCAGAGUUGGGGGAAGAAUCACUCAGGCACUCGGGCUGCUCCUCCCAGCCUGUGCUGCGUCAUUGCUGCUGCUGCUCACAGACAGGUAGCCGGCAGGCUUGGGGCUGCUGGUGCACUAGCUGACAUACUCACACCAAGGACUACUGUAAAAAUGAGGCAGGUACAUGACAUAGUAGUGAAGGAAGAAGGCUCUGGAAUGGCUGAGGGUUUCAGUGGGACGGGUUCCUCCUGAGAGAAUCUGACCGUGGAGAUCUCCAGAUCAGACCAGUUGCUUCCUGAAGAGGGGUGCUCCAUCACCACCUCCCUAUCUUUAUGCUUUCGGAUUUCUAAAUGAGAGAGUCAUCCAGAAACUCGAGGGGUGGAGAGCAUUUGUCAGUGACUGUCCUUUGGUCCCCAAGGGGCUCCUCAGUGGGUUUCUCCUGAGGGUCUGUGACUACUCUCCUGUCACAGAAGCUGCUCCUCUCUGGCACUGUCUUGUCCUUCUCCACUGACCUCUGGGAUUGACUAUCCUUCUCAGCAGGGGUGACUGUGACACUCCUGGCUGUUCCUUCUCAGUCUUGGCUGGUCCUUCACUCCUAGCUGGUCCUUCUCCACAACUGGGACACUCUGCUAUGCUUGGUUUUGAACUAGUGACAGCCUCUCCCUUCCUUUUCGGCAUUGAUUUCCCUGGAUGCCCUGGUUAGCCUCCAGGUAGAUCAUUGUGGAGCCCUGAUGUCGAAGUCUAUCCGUCUUCCUUUUCUGGACCUUGUUGGGUUCCUCAGUCGUAUCAUUCUGACUCUCAGCUUCAGUUGCAAAUUAAGAGUUCAUGGAGUUACGAGAACUAUCUUUGGAAUCAGCCUUAAAGCUGCAGGCUUCCUUUUCUAGAGAAGCUAUUUCUUCUAGAAAGGGAUUGGUAGGAUGUGGAGGGGUUCCCCCUGACGAAAGGACUCCCUGAGUGCUCUGAAUCAGGCAGCCUUUGGUGGCGGCCCCGCCCACACCUGUGCCCGAGGAAUGCCGGGGAGGAAUGUAAGAGUUAAAGAAAGGAAAGAAACAGGAAAAGCGGCUCAACAGUCAAAGACAGGUUUGUUUUGGACAAUAAACCUGAGAGGGCCUUCUGGCCGAGUUAGGUCAGAGUCACUCUCUCUUACAGGCUAAGAGUAUUUAAGGGUUCAGGGCAGAAGAGGUUAUCACAGGCUUGGAAUGUUUCUGUAUCUCUUCGCCUUGCUUAUCUGGGAGGGGGAGGUUUUGUGUCUGUUCCCAUACAACUCCCUGCAGCUGCAGGGAUACCCCCCCCACCUCCUAGUCUGCUUUUAGCUUGUCUAUCUUAGCGCAUUUAAAGGGAAAGGAAUGUGCUUAUUAGGGCCUACUUUUUUACUGGGGCCCAUUUUUGGGGGCCCAUUUACACUCCCAAAACAUGAGUGUGAAGUUCGGUGGUUACCCAAGAGACUUGGGUGCCCAGCUGUGCCCAGCUGUCUUAUCUGUGUUUUACUGUCUACUCUUUCUGGCUGCUUUUUGUUAGAAGUGAUUUCCUUGAAACGUAAGAAGUUAGAAAGGGAGCUGGAACUGAAAAUGGGGGUGUUUGUCCAAGAUGACGGUGCUCCUGCUCUGUCAUUCCAGACCCUAUAGUUAUAAAAGGACCAGGGGCGACGUGUUCUUUCUGGUUACUUCCUGCUGGGUGGGAGAGGUAGAGAGUCCCUUGGUCUCGGAUUGACUGCGGGAGCAAUGCCGUCUGUAGAUGUUUUGGAUAGUUGUCUGUGAAAUAGCCAUGCUCCUGUCAGUUAAGAAUCUUUGAAAAAGGUUAAUUAGGCAGGGUAAAAACAUUAGUCCUAGGCUUAUUAUUAGGAGAGGGCCCAGGAAUGGGAUGACCCAUGGUAUGCUUUUUGUUCCCAAACCAAUAAUUCAUUUGGUUGUUUUGGUAUUCGCUUAGCAUUUUAGCCCUUUGUUUGAGAUUUUUAGCAGCCUCUCUUACGAGACCUGAUUGGUUGAGAUAGAAGCAACAUUUCUUUCCCAAUGAGAGGCAGAGGCACAUGUUUGGAAAGACCCAUGUGUUAUUUUUUAUUAGUAACUGUUAUUCCUGCUGUAAGGAUAGUAAUUAAGCAAAAUGCUACGGUAAUUGAGAUUGUCUGUCUGAUAUCCUACCCUCAGGGUGCUGCAGUACAUAGUCCUACUGCAAAUAGUCCAGUAAAGCAGUUCCCGCAAGGGUGGCAUGGUAAAUAAUUUCCAUAAAAAAGCUUUAAUAUUUGGCUUAAAAGGAGAGGUAGAAAUGACAAAAAGUACUUGGUGAGGUAAGAGUGAGACUGAGUCAGAUGAGUAAUUGUCACUCAGUUAGUUAUUUUUUAUGAUUUUCAACUUAAGAUUUCUUAUUUCUUUACAUUGAUAUUUAGGACGUUCCUCUGGGCUGUUGGGAUUGCUUCCUCAGCUUUUCAGGCUUUGACUUGAGUGUGAUGUAUGCAGGGGUUGAUUCCUGUAACAGAUGUAAUUUAAACUGUCGAAAACCAUAAAAAUUGAAAAACAUCAGUCAAGACUAGAAUUUAACAGGUGUGCUAUAGUUUUUGAAACCUAAUUUUCUCUCUCCAGUUUACCAUUUUUAUUAAAAGACAAAUCAUAAUAGGACUGGUUUGCUUUAUUAUACUUGGCUUAUUUAUUUGUAUACAGUGCAGCAAGAGUAAUUAUUUGCUACAUACACCUUUUAAAUUGGCUUUGAUGGAACUUUUUUCCAUAGAAGGAAUCAGAUAAGACUUUCCAAAGCCAAACCCAGCCAUGGAUUUGUACCAUUAAAUACCUAUGAGUUGGGUGAAUUCCUUUCCUCUUGAGGUUUCAAGAUAACUUGGGGUUCCUGGCCUGUCAAAGUGACAUGCUUUGCUUAGCACAGGUCAGAAACUCUGUACAGGGACUGUGUACACAGAAUAUGAGACCAGUUUCCAAGGGCUUUCUUGGCUUCCUAAGUCAAGUUCGAUUCCUUAAAGGAGAGCACACCAUUCCAGUGAAAGCCUUGGCAGAAUAACCAGUUUCUCCAAUUGUGUUCUGUUACGCAAGAAAAUAUAUUCUUACCGCACUGAUGCACACAACUAUAUUGUUGUGGUUUAAGAAUACUUAUAACUAGUUUUCAAAUUCUAGAGGAACUAGGCAGAGAGAAACAAACAUCUUUAAAUCCUAAUAUUUACAGGAGUAUAUUUAGUUUAAGACAAGUUUCCUUGACUCUGGAAAAUAAAAUAAGGAUUGGCAGUGUCCUGUUCGGAUACAAUCAGAAACACAAUUGACAAAUAAAUUUGGUUAUUUCUGUGGUUUACAGUAACCCAACAUAACCUUACUUGUGAUUAAUAGCACAUAUUUAGAUACUAGAACCUUAGACAUCCCAUACAGUUUUAGAACAUAUGUUAAUAUUAUUCCCUCAAAUAAAACCUAUUGGACAUUAUCUUGACAAUUUCAUGUACCUAAACAUGUUAAAUAAUCCUGUUUACCUCUUUUCUGGAUGCUCCAGGGGCCUUCUGCAGCACCCAAAGGCCGGGGGUUAGGAAAGACAACCUUGAGACUAAAGUUUGAUUUGGGGAAGCCUGUUAAAUAUGUUGAAAAUUUGAAACACUUGAUAGUAUGAAAUAGAACUUUAGAUUACCAUUAAGUUUUUGCUUCGCCAAAAUGAUGAGUUAAACAUUUGAAAGCAAAAACCAUUCCUCAUCCUUUUUAUUACAUAAAAAUCCUCUUUAAGAGAGAAAGUUGAAUUUUAUCCUUGCAUUCGUUUGCUAUUAAUAUUAACCCUAAUUUUUAAUGAAACCUUAUAGACAAUCCUAUUUAAAAAAAAUUUUUUUUUAAUUACACUUUAAGUUCUAGGGUACAUGUGCACAACGUGCAGGUUUGUUACAUAUGUAUACAUGUGCCAUGUUGGUGUGCUGCACCCAUUAACGCAUCAUUUACAUUAGGUAUAUCUCCUAAUGCUGUCCCUCCAACCUCCCCCCACCCUACGACAGGCCCUGUUGUGUGAUGUUCCCCACCCUGUGUCCAAGUGUUCUCAUUGUUCAUUUCCCACCUAUGAGUGAGAGUAUGUGGUAUUUGGUUUUCUGUGCUUGGCGAUAGUUUGCUCAGAAUGAUGGUUUCCAGCUUCAUCCAUGUCCCUGCAAAGGACAUGAACUCAUCCUUUUUUAUGGCUGCAUAGUAUUCCAUGGUGUAUAUGUGUCACAUUUUCUUAAUCCAGUCUAUCAUUGAUGAACAUUUGGGUUGGUUCCAAGUCUUUGCUGUUGGGAAUAGUGCUGCAAUAAACAUACGUGUGCAUGUGUCUUUAUAGUAGCAUGAUUUGUCAUCCUUUGGGUAUAUAUCCAGUAAUGGGAUGGCUAGGUCAAAUGGUAUUUCUAGUUCUAGAUCCUUGAGGAAUUGCCACACUGUCUUCCACAACGGUUGAACUAGUUUACACUCCCACCAACAGUGUAAAAGUGUUCCUCUUUCUCUACAUCCUCUCCAGGACCUGUUGUUUCCUGACGUUUUAAUGAUUGCCAUUCUAACUGGUGUGAGUUGAUAUCUCAUUGUGGUUUUGAUUUGCAUUUCUCUGAUGGCCAGUGAUGAUGAGCAUUUUUUCAUGUGUCUUUUGGCUGCAGAAAUGCCUUCUUUUGAGAAGUGUCUGUUCAUAUCCUUCACCCACUUUUUGAUGGGAUUGUUUGAUGCUUUCUUGUAAAUUUAAGUUCUUUGUAGAUUCUGGAUAUUAGCCCUUUAUCAGAUGAGUAGAUAGCAAAAAUUUUCUGCCAUUCUGUAGGUUGCCUGUUCACUCUGAUGGCAAUUUCUUUUGCUGUGCAGAAGCUCUUUAGUUUAAUUAGAUCCCAUAUGUCUAUUUUGGCUUUUGUUGCCAUUGCUUUUGGUGUUUUAGUCAUGAAGUCCUUGCCCAUGCCCAUGUCCUGAAUGGCAUUGCCUAGGUUUUCUUCUAGGGUUUUUAUGGUUUUAGGUCUAACAUUUAAGUCUUUAAUCCAUCUUGAAUUAAUUUUUGUAUAGGGUGUAAGGAAGAGAUCCCAUUUCAGCUUUCUACAUAUGGCUAGCCAGUUUUCCCAGCACCAUUUAUCAAAUAGGGAAUCCUUUCCCCAUUUCUUGUUUUUGUCAGGUUUGUCAAAGAUCAGAUGGUUGUAGAUGUGUGAUAUUAUUUCUGAGGGCUCUGUUCUGUUCCCUUGUUCUACAUCUCUGUUUUGUUACCAGUACCAUGCUGUUUUGGUUACUGUAGCCUUGUAGUAUAGUUUAAAGUCAGGUAGCAUGAUGUUCCAGCUUUGUUCUUUUUGCUUAGGAUUGUCUUGGCAAUGUGGGCUCUUUUUUGGCUCCAUAUAAACUUUAAAGUAGUUUUUUCCAAUUCUGUGAAGAAAGUCCUUGGUAGCUUAAUGUGGAUGGCAUUGAAUCUAUAAAUUACCUUGGGCAGUAUGGCCAUUUUCACGAUAUUGAUUCUUCCUAUCCAUGAGCAUGGAAUGUUCUUCCAUUUGUUUGUGUCCUCUUUUAUUUCGUUGAGCAGUGGUUUGUAGUUCUCCUUCAAGAGGUCCUUCACAUCCCUUGUAAGUUGGAUUCCUAGGUAUUUUAUUCUCUUUGAAGCAAUUGUGAAUGGGAGUUCACUCAUGAUUUGGCUCUUUGUUUGUCUGUUAUUGGUGUAUAGGAAUGUUUGUGAUUUUUGCACAUUGAUUUUGUAUCCUGAGACUUUCCUAAAGUUGCUUAUCAGCUUAAGGAGAUUUUGGGCUGAGACGAUGGGGUUUUCUAGAUAUACAAUCAUGUCAUCUGCAAACAGGGACAAUUUGACUUCCUUUUUUCCUAAUUGAAUACCCUUUAUUUCUUUCUCCUGCCUGACUGCCCGGGCCAGAACUUCCAAUACUAUGUUGAAUAGGAGUGGUGAGAGAGGGCAUCCCUGUCUUGUGCCAGUUUUCAAAGGGAAUGCUUCCAGUUUUUGCCCAUUCAGUAUGAUAUUGGCUGUGGGUUUGUCAUAAAUAGCUCUUAUUAUUUUGAGAUACGUCCCAUCAACACCUAGUUUAUUGAGAGUUUUUAGCAUGAAGCGCUGUUGAAUUUUGUCAGAGGCCUUUUCUGCAUCUAUUGAGAUAAUCACGUGGUUUUUGUCUUUGGUUCUGUUUAUAUGCUGGAUUACAUUUAUAGAUUUGUAUAUGUUGAACCAGCCUUGCAUCCCAGGGAUGAAGCCAACUUGAUCGUGGUGGAUAAGCUUUUUGAUGUGCUGCUGGAUUCGGUUUGCCAGUAUUUUAUUGAGGAUUUUCACAUCAAUGUUCAUCAGGGAUAUUGGUCUAAAAUUCUCUUUUGUUGUGUCUCUGGCCAGGCUUUGGUGUCAGGAUGAUGCUGGCCUCAUAAAAUGAGUUAGGGAGGAUUCCUUCUUUUUCUAUUGAUUGGAAUAGUUUCAGAAAGAAUAAUAGCAACUCCUCCCUGUACCUCUGGUAGAAUUCGGCUGUGAAUCCGUCUGGUCCUGGACUUUUUUUCGUUGGUAAGCUAUUAAUUAUUGCCUCAAUUUCAGAGCCUGUUAUUGGUCUAUUAAGAGAUUCAGCUUCUUCCUGGUUUCGUCUUGGGAGAGUGUAUGUGUCCAGGAAUUUAUCUAUUUCUUCCAGAUUUUCUAGUUUAUUUGAGUAGAGGUGUUUAUAGUACUCUCUGAUGGUAGUUUGUAUUUCUGUGGGUUCGGUGGUGAUAUCCCCUUCAUCAUUUUUUAUUGCAUCUAUUUGGUUCUUCUCUCUUCUUUAUUAAUCUUGCUAGCGGUCUAUUUUGUUGAUCUUUUCAAAAAACCAGCUCCUGGAUUCAUUGAUUUUUUUGAAGGGUUUUUUUUGUGUCUCUAUCUCCUUCAGUUCUGCUCUGAUCUUAGUUAUUUCUUGCCUUCUGCUAGCUUUUGAAUGUGUUUGCUCUUGCUUCUCUAGUUCUUUUAAUGGUGAUGUUAGGGUGUCAAUUUUAGAUCUUUCCCGCUUUCUCUUGUGGGCAUUUAGUGCUAUAAAUUUUCCUCUACACACUUCUUUAAAUGUGUCCCAGAGAUUCUGGUAUGUUGUGUCUUUGUUCUCAUUGGUUUCAAAGAACAUCUUUAUUUCUGCCUUCAUUUCGUCAUUUACCCAGUAGUCAUUCAGGAGCAGGUUGUUCAGUUCCCAUGUAGUUGUGAGGUUUUGAGUGAGUUUCUUAAUCCUGAGUUCUAAUUUGAUUGCACUGUGGUCUGAGAGACAGUUUGUUAUAAUUUCUGUUCUUUUACAUUUGCUGAGGAGUGCUUUACUUCCAACUAUGUGGUCAAUUUUGGAAUAAGUAUGAUGUGGUGCUGAGAAGAAUGUAUAUUCCAUUGAUUAGGGAUGGAGAGUUCUGUAGAUGUCUGUUAGACCUGCUUGGUGCAGAGCUGAGUUCAAGUCCCGGAUAUCCUUGUUAGCUUUCUGUCUUGUUGAUCUGUCUAAUGUUGACAGUGGGGUGUUAAAGUCUCCCAUUAUUAUUGUGUGGAAGUCUAAGUCUCUUUGUAGGUCUCUAAGGACUUGCUUUAUGAAUCUGGUUGCUCCUGUAUUGGGUGCAUAUAUAUUUAGGAUAGUUAGCUCUUCUUGUUGCAUUGAUCCCUUUACCAUUAUGUAAUGGCCUUCUUUGUCUCUUUUGAUCUUUGUUGGUUUAAAGUUUGUUUUAUCAGAGACUAGGAUUGCAACCCCUGCUUUUGUUGUUGUUGUUGUUGUUGUUUUCCAUUUGCUUGGUAGAUAUUCAUCCAUCCCUUUAUUUUGAGCCUAUGUGUGUCUCUGCACGUGAGAUGGGUCUCCUGAAUACAUCAUACUGAUGGGUCUUGACUCUUUAUCCAAUUUGCCAGUCUGUGUCUUUUAAUUGGGGCAUUUAGCCCAUUUACGUUUAAGGUUAAUAUUGUUAUGUGUGAAUUUGAUCCUGCCAUUAUGAUAUUAGCUGGUUAUUUUGCUUGUUAGUUGAUGCUGUUUCUUCCUAGCAUUGAUGGUCUUUACAGUUUGGCAUGUUUUUGCAGUGGCUGGUACCGUUGUUCCUUUCCAUGUUUAGUGCUUCCUUCAGGAGCUCUUGUAAGGCAGGCCUGGUGGUGACAAAAAUCUCUCAGCAUUUGCUGUCUGUAAAGGAUUUUAUUUCUCCUUCACUUAUGAAGCUUAGUUUGGCUUGAUACGAAACUCUGGGUUGAAAAGUGUUUUCUUUAAGAAUGUUGAAUAUUGGCCCCCACUCUUCUGGCUUGUAGAGUUUCUGCUGAGAGAUCAGCUAUUAUUCUGAUGGGCUUCCCUUUGUGAGUAACCUGACCUUUCUCUCUGGCUGCCCUUAACAUUUUUUCGUUCAUUUCAACCUUGGUGAAUCUGACAAUUAUGUGUCUUGGGGUUGCUCUUCUCAAGGAGUAUCUUUGUGGCGUUCUCUGUAUUUCCUGAAUUUGAAUGCUGGCCUGCCUUGCUAGGUUGGGGAAGUUCUCCUGGGGGAUAAUAUCCUGAAGAGUGUUUUCCAACUUGGUUCCAUUCUCUCUGUCACUUUCAGAUACAACAAUCAAACAUAGAUUUGGUCUUUUCACAUAGUCCCAUAUUUCUUGGAGGCUUUGUUCGUUUCUUUUUACUCUUUUUUCUCUGAACUUCUCUUCUUGCUUCAUUUCAUUCAUUUGAUCUUCAGUUACUGAUACCCUUUCUUCCACUUGAUCGAAUCGGCUACUGAAGCUUGUGCAUGCGUCACGUAGUUCUUAUGCCAUGGUUUUCAGCUCCAUCAGGUCGUUUAAGGUCUUCUCUGUGCUGUUUAUUCUAGUUAGCCAUUUGUCUAAUCUUUUUUCAAGGUUUUUAGCUUCUUGGCGAUGGGUUCGAACAUCCUCCUUUAGCUCGGAGAAGUUGGUUAUUACCGAUCUUCUGAAGCCUACUUCUGUCAACUCGUCAAAGUCAUUCAGAGGAAGGAGUUUUGGAGGAAGGAGAGACCUAGGGAGGGUUUUUUGUUUUGUUUUUGUAAGAGAAGGAUGUUGGCCAGGCGCGGUGGCUCACGCCUAUAAUCCCAGCACUUUGGGAGGCCAGUGCAGGCCGAUCAUGAGGUUAGGAGAUUGAGACCAUCCUGGCCAACAUGGUGAAAUGCCGUCUGUACUAAAAUACAAAAAAUUAGCCAGGCGUGAUGGUACACACCUGUAGUCCCAGCUACUUGGGAGGCUGAGGCAGGAGAAUUACUUGCACCUGGGAGGCAGAGGUUGCAGUGAGCUGAGAUUGCGCCACUGCACUCCAGCCUGGCGACACAGCGAGACUCCGUCUCAAAAAAAAAAAAAAAAAAAAAAGGAGGAUGUCAUGAGGGGUGCAAGGUUGACAUAGAGAGGGUAGAGGAAAGCCUGAGUAUAGGGAACCUCUUGCCAUUUGCCAUUCCUGGUGAUAAAAUUGUCAAGGUCCCUGAGAAUCUGAAAGUUAAAGGGUGCUGUUCUCAGGCAAUUGGCUGUUAUUAUCUUGUUUGUAUUGGGACCAGGCCAUAUUGCAAUAAAAAACUAAACACUUUG